GAUUCCAUGACACCCCCACCUUCUAAUUCUGUUAUUGCAACUGCAGACCGUUACCUGGUACGCUGGCUGCUACCUCCCUCACUCUUGUCAGAGUCGGAGCUACAGGCAGUGCCUUCAGCUCUGAGCUCAGGCAUCCCGGUCCCUGUUUUUGCGGUUAAGGACUCUAAAGUGUUGUGUCGUGUUCAUCAACUUUUUCUCAACCUCCCUGGCUCUACCUCUUCUGCCACAAACGUCAGCAUGGUGGUAUCUGCCGACCCUUUGUCCAGCGAGAGGGCAGAGAUGAACAUCCUAGAAAUCAACCAGGAAUUGCGCUCGCAGCUGGCAGAGAGCAAUCAGCAGUUCCGAGACCUCAAAGAGAAAUUCCUUAUAACUCAAGCUACUGCCUACUCCCUGGCCAACCAGCUGAAGAAAUACAAGUGUGAAGAGUACAAAGACAUCAUAGACUCUGUGCUGAGGGAUGAACUGCAGUCCAUGGAGAAGCUGGCAGAGAAGCUCAGGCAAGCUGAGGAGCUCAGGCAGUAUAAAGCCCUGGUUCACUCUCAGGCAAAAGAGCUGACCCAGUUACGGGAGAAGUUACGGGAAGGGAGAGAUGCCUCCCGCUGGCUGAACAAGCAUCUGAAAACCCUCCUCACUCCUGAUGACCCUGACAAGUCCCAGGGUCAGGACCUCCGAGAGCAGCUGGCUGAGGGGCACAGGCUGGCAGAGCACCUUGUUCACAAGCUGAGCCCAGAAAAUGAUGAAGAUGAAGAUGAGGAUGAAGACGACAAAGACGAGGAGGUUGAGAAAGUACAGGAAUCACCUGCCCCCAGGGAGGUGCAGAAGACUGAAGAAAAGGAAGUCCCUCAGGACUCACUGGAGGAAUGUGCUGUCACUUGUUCAAAUAGUCACAACCCUUCUAACUCCAACCAGCCUCACAGGAGCACCAAAAUCACAUUUAAGGAACACGAAGUUGACUCUGCUCUGGUUGUAGAGAGUGAACACCCUCAUGAUGAAGAGGAGGAAGCUCUAAACAUUCCCCCAGAAAAUCAAAAUGACCAUGAGGAGGAGGAGGGGAAAGCGCCAGUGCCCCCCAGGAACCGACAAUCACUUGAACCAGGUGAACUGACCAACCUCAGGGAUUUCCUGAUCUCACCUGUGGUCUCCCAUGUGGCUAAUCCAGGACACCAUGACAAGUCCAACUCUUACCGGCAUCGUGAAGUCUCUUUCUUGGCAUUGGAUGAACAGAAAGUUUGCUCCGCUCAGGAUGUUGCCAGGGAUUACUCCAAUCCCAAAUGGGAUGAAACCUCACUUGGCUUCCUCGAAAAGCAAAGUGAUCUUGAAGAGGUGAAAGGACAAGAAACAGUUGCUCCCAGGCUCAGCAGGGGACCGCUGAGAGUGGACAAGCAUGAAAUCCCCCAGGAGUCACUGGAUGGAUGUUGCUUGACUCCUUCCAUCCUUCCUGACCUGACUCCCUCCUACCACCCUUAUUGGAGCACUUUGUACUCUUUUGAAGACAAGCAAGUCAGCUUGGCUCUUGUAGACAAAAUUAAAAAGGAUCAAGAGGAGAUAGAAGACCAAAGCCCACCAUGCCCCAGGCUCAGCCAGGAGCUGCCAGAGGUGAAGGAGCAGGAAGUCCCAGAGGACUCUGUGAAUGAAGUUUACUUGACUCCCUCAGUUCACCAUGACGUGUCUGACUGCCACCAGCCUUAUAGCAGCACCUUGUCCUCAUUGGAGGAUCAGCUUGCCUGCUCUGCUCUGGAUGUAGCCUCCCCCACCGAGGCGGCCUGUCCCCAAGGGACUUGGAGUGGAGACUUGAGCCACCACCAGUCAGAGGUGCAAGUUUCACAGGCACAGCUGGAACCAAGCACCCUGGUGCCCAGUUGUCUGCGACUACAGCUGGAUCAAGGGUUCCACUGUGGGAACGGCUUGGCCCAGCGGGGCCUUUCCUCCACCACCUGCAGCUUCUCAGCCAAUGCUGAUUCUGGGAACCAAUGGCCCUUCCAAGAGCUGGUUUUAGAGCCCUCUCUGGGGAUGAAGAACCCUCCCCAGCUGGAAGAUGAUGCACUUGAAGGCUCAGCAAGCAACACACAAGGGCGUCAAGUCACUGGCCGGAUUCGUGCCUCCCUUGUCCUGAUACUGAAGACCAUCAGAAGAAGACUCCCGUUCAGCAAGUGGAGACUGGCAUUCAGAUUCACUGGCCCGCAUGCUGAGAGUGCAGAGAUACCAAAUACUGCUGGAAGGACGCAAAGGAUGGCAGGAUGAAAGAAUGUCACAAAAAGCAGCUUUUCCACUUGAUAAAAACAACUAAAACAGCAAAGCAAGUUUAAGUCCAAACACAAUACUGCAGGGGUCCUUCACUGAGGAUUGAAUUUCAGACACAGAAUACUCUUGAUGACUUCAAGCCACUAUGCUCCUUUGAUUUGAGAAGCCACAUUCCAUCCCCCUCCAAUUGUGACCAAUACCUAGGGAGACCAAUGCCCAGAUGGACAAAUAGCAUUGACCGGCGUUAGCCCUGUUUCUCAAUUCCCAUCGUGUAGAGAACAGGAGUCCGCAGCUGCUGGCAGGAGACAGCAUGUCAGCCGGGACUCUGCCAGGGCAGAGUAUGAGCAAUGCCAUGUUCUUGCUGAAAACGCUUAGCCUGAGUUUCAUAGGCGGUAACCCUCAGAUAACUGCAGAAUGUAGAACAUUGAACAGGACAACUGACCUGUCUCCUUCAAACAGUCCAUGUCACCACCAAGAACACAACAAAAAGGAGAAGAGACAUUUUGAGUUCAAAAAGAGUAAAAAGCCUAUGCAGCUUAUGCUUUUUUAGUCAUUUUGAACCCAAAACAUCUCCUCAUCUUUUUGUUGUUGUCAUUGAUGGUGGUGACAUGGACUUGUUUGUGGAGGACAGGUCAGCUGUCUGGCUCAAUGGUCUACAUUCUGAAGUUAUCUGAAAAUGUCGUCAUGAUUAAAUUCAGCCUAAACAUUUUGCCAGGAACUCUGCAGAGUCCAUGCUGUGAGCUUCCUACCUCAGCCCAUCUGCAGGCAGAGAAGGCCCAGUGUGUCCAUCCCCAGUGCGGUGAUACUAGGAUGGUCACUUGGUUAAGGAGGGGUCUAGGAGCUCUGUCCCUUGUAAAGACAUCUUAUUUGUAAGUAAUUUGGAAAGUGGUUUGAAAUAGUAUAAAUAUCCUGUAUUCUAGUGAUCUUCUUCAGAACAUUUUAUCACCAAUUAAUCACCCCGUCUGUGUCAGUUAUUAUAUUUAAGUUUGUACAUUGAAAAUUGUCUAUCUCAAAAUCUUACCUUAUACUUGCUUUUGCUGGCAUUCUUCGUAAAAAAGAUCAUUCCCUGCCCAAAUUUUAACUUUCAUCCAAAAUUAAUUUUAAUUUCUUUUUGCUGGCAUUCUGUUGUGAAAAAGAAUAUUCUCUGCCCCAAUUAUAACUUUCAUCCAAAAUUAAUUUUAGUCCAUCAGUUAAAAUUUUAAGUUUUAAAUCUGUUUAAUUAAAACAUUUCUUGCCUCUCA